GGGUAUUUACUGAUCCAGUGAGUGAAGGUGGGCCCGGCCGGGCUGGUUCCCAUCCUCUGAUCAACGCCUAGGGGAACCAGUGAACUCCAAUGCUGACCAUAAGAGUUUCAGAAAGUAGGGCUGGAAAGCCCAGCCCUCCGCUCAGAGACCUGUGAAGAUCGAGGAGGAUGGCGCAUAUGCUGCCGCAGGAUGGAAACCUCGAUCAGAGAAGGCUGGGGCAGUUCCGGGACAUAAAGCGCGCUGGAAGGACACUGAGUCACCAACCACCGCCAUGGGCCGGAAGCCACCGCCCUCGCGUCAACUGCAAUCUAGAGCGCGGCGCAUCCCGUGAGCCCGCGGGGAACUACGACUCCCGGCAUGCUCCGCGGCCACCGGAAUUAACCCUUCAGGGCUGGGGGCCGCGCUAUGCCCCGCCCCCUCCCCAGCCCCAGACACGGACCCCGCAGGCCAACUGGCUCCCUGCCCCUGCCCCCGCCCCUUGACAUCCCAGACUCCCUGGCUAUUUAAACAGAGAUGGGUGCCCCCAUCCGCACACU